UGGGCUCAAGCAAUCCUCCCAUCUUGGCCUUCCAAGGUGCCAGAAUCAUAGGUGUGAGCCACCAUUAAGGCGAUUCUUAAAAAUGAUACAUAAAGCACAGAGAGCACAUAAAACAUGACAGUUAAAGAAGAAAACCAAAAGUGGGAAUAUAAGGUGGACCCAGGAAUUGUCCUAAGAAAUGUACCCCAAAUGACUAUGGACCUGAUCCACAGCUUUCUCACAGCUUUUAAAAAAAGAAAACCUUAAUUACACAAAUCACAAAAACAAGCUGUUUGCUGAAAGGGAACCAUGACUGUUCUUGGUAUUAAGCCGAGGGGCUGGCAUAAAGAGAUUGCCAUGGGGCAAUGGCUACUGGCACAGAUAGGGCCCCUCCAAGAAGCACAUGGUUAAUCCAGCCUUUUUGUUAAAGGAUAUUUUUCUUAGAAAAAGGUAAAAUCAUGCUCUCAUCAAGGUAUACAAUGAGUGUGUUAAAAACCUUAUUUCGCUCAUUAUUAAUGAUGGAACCAGGCAAAUGUUACCAUUGGUUCAAAGGAGAAGUCAAAAGAAUACAAAUUUACUUGGACUUUAAUUAACAAAUAGAUGAGAAACUGACUUCUUCCACUGAGUAGGAGGUAGAGAAAAAAGUCCAGAGAACUCCCACCAGAAAGAACUUAUUUGUAUAUCUCUGGUCAAGAAUCAAGAAUUAUAUUGGAUUGCUAUAUUGCUGUCUAUAUAAUUUAGAAAGUUGCAGAGUCUCUCAAAAGCAAUAAAAGGCUGGAGUCAGAUAAUCAGCGAGCGUGCUCUAAACAGUGCAAGUUUUCCACUGGAGACACCUAGUGAUCUUUUUUUGCUUAUUCCAAAUUUCUUUACAUUUUAAAAAUACUGGUCUUAGUAGGCUCGCGGAGUUUAUAAUCAGCUCAAAGCCUAAGCCUGUUUAAGAUACGCUGCUGGUAAGUGCUGGCUCCCUGACGCCUAACAAAAGAUUUUGAUGCCGCCAACCUCCUACAUUUUAUGUGGCUUCUCAUUGCCUCAGAGGUCAAAUCCAAAAUCUGUCUUAGCAUUUGUUCCUGCAUUUGUUUACUCUUCCUUUAUCUAGCAACUGUUUAUUUUUGCCACAGUGCAAAUAAGCCAGUCCUCACCCCCUUGGAGGACUGCUAUAGUAGAUGGAUAGAGGUUAUGAUGACUCUGUGUGUGUGUGUGUACGUGUGUGUGUGUGCACGCACGUGUGUGCGUGUGUGUGUGCAUUUUCAGGAAGGAUGUUGGGAAUGUAAUAGUUAUGAAAAAGGAACAAGGAGUGUAUAGAAAUAUAUUAGAAGAAGGAGGUCCAGAAAGAAUAGUCCAGGAGGAGGGAAGUCCAUGGGGGCCAAGAAACCUCAUGAUCCACUGGAGAAACCACAGGUGCUUCCUGAUAGCUGGGGUGAAGCAGAGUUGGAAGGAGGGUUGGAAAGAGCGAGGGAGGAACUUAGAAUUCCCUUGGAGUGAAUUCAUAUAUGCCCUGCCAGGGAGUUUGCAGGUCAUUCUCAACACAACGAGAAGCUAUGAACAUUUCCAGAUUUGGCUUUUGGAAAGAUGUCUGUGGAAGCAAGGGAUGGAGGGAUGGACAGAGUGGAUGAGGGUAUUCCCAGCCUGUUUUCCAAUCCAUUUUUCUAACCUUAUUUGCCAUCAUGUCUUAAAAACAAAUACAAAAACAAAAAACAAAAACUUCAGUCCAGGCUAAGUGGCCCAAUGGCUGUCUCAUUGAGUAGGCUUUGUUCAUGUUCCUAAAUAGGAGCAUCUUUUGUUCCUGAUUUCUUCACUUCCACCUACUCUUGGGGCAGGCUCAGGGGCCGUGGCUCACGCCUGUAAUCCCAGCAGUUUGGGAGGCCGAGGCGGGUGGAUCACUUGAGGUCAGGGGUUUGAGACCAGCCUGGCCAACAUGAUGAAACCCCAUCUCUACUACAAAUACAAAAAAACUAGCUGGACGUGGUGGUGUGCACCUGUAACCCCAGCUACUUGGGAGGCUGAGGCAGGAGACUCGCUUGAACCCGGGAGGUGGAGGUUGCAGUGAGCAGAGAUCGUGCCACUGCACUCCAGCCUGGGCAACAAGAGUGAAACUCUGUCUCAAAAAAAAAAAAAAAAAAAAAAAAAGAAGAAGAAGAAGAAGCUUCAGUUGUCCCGAGCACAACUUCUGGGUGCCAAUUUUUCACGUUUCUCAUUUUCGAGUCAAGUGUAUAAUAUCUCUUGACUGUGUCUGGAAUUUCUCUCAACAUAAACGGUAAGUCCCUGGAGGGCAAGAAUCAUCCCGAUCAACAACACACACUGGCCAUAUCACUGACUCCUUCAUCAUUAUGACAAAUAUUAAAGUUGAAUUCGAGUUUCCUUUCCUCUUGCUGCUACCUAGGAGGCAUUUGCCAUCACUUGAGGGAUGCUUGGGAAUGCAAACUAACUUUAAUAAUAAUUAAGGCAAAAUAAUAAGUAAUAAUUAACACAAAUCUGCUAAUUAGUGCAAUUUUUCUCAUUGUUAUUAACUGUAACCAUUUAUUAGUCUGAACAGAUGUUGAUUACUGGCCACCAGAGGUAAAGCAUCCCAAGUUCAAUGGGGGGAGAUGGGCUCAGAGUUUGCUGUGAUCCACAGGUAAAAUAAGGAACUCUGAUCUUAUCACAUUUGUUGUGUGUUUUUGCUUAGCAUUUAAGUUCAAGACUUUUAUGGGUAUAGCCACUUAAUGUCAUUGCGUCACUUAAUGUAAUGGGUGUGAUGAUACAUGUAUGUGUCAUCUUUGGACAUCUUUGGACAUCAGGAUACUGGGACCAUCACCCUUUUGAAUCCUGGCCCCACCUGUUUAUUAUUCCAAGUUGCCCUUGAUUCACCCCUGAGUUUCUUGACAUAUUUGCAUCAUGACCUCCAGUCAUUAGCUUUAAGCCUUGCUAGUUGAUUCAUUUUCUUUCAUUCAUUUAUUUGUUCAUUCAACAAAUAUUUUCAAGUGCUUGCGAUGCCUGGUGUUUUGCUGUUUUUCUUGUAUUUUUUUAAAGAUAGUCUUUAAAACUCACAGUCUAAACAAAUACGAGACAAAACAUGGAAGGCAAUAAGCUGCAAUUAAAGAUUUUGUUUUUGGAAAUGGUCAUUAGGCUUAAAAAUAGUCACAGGGUCAGUUUUUCACGAAGCCAAUGCAGGGUAAAAGGCUAAUCUCACUUGUAAUUCUUAGCAGCUCUCUCACUGAUGGUUUAGUUACUUAAUCUCCUUGGUGUUUACUGUGUCGUUCCUUACGGGUGAAGAAUGGGAGAUGAACGGGAAUGCUUUGUCUAAAGCACAGAAGAGUUGCUGGAAAUUUUAAGACUCACCAGUCAGGCAACAUCAUCUAUCAAAAAGUUCUCAUAGAAUGUAACAAAUAAUCAUGGAACCUACUCAAAUAAUGCAGAACCUUUGUCCAUAGCUUCAGGCCUCCAAUGCUUUCCUUCUCUCUUUGGAUGUGAAAUGCACAAGGCAGGUUGGACUCUGUAUACUGAUCUGUUGCAAAGGUAUCGGGCUUUUAGAAUAAAUGGUUGACCAUGACAAUGAAAAGAUGAGAAUGUAGGGAGGUUGGGCUUACUUUUCUCCUGCUGAAAGUUGAUUCCGGGUAGCAUCUGAACUUCACAAGCUGAGAAUUCCAAUAAAUCCACAAAAAGAAUUCCCCUAGGGAAGGGGGUGUGGACUUUAAUUGAUGAUGUCCAAUUAGAGUUUCCAUUGACAUUGCCAUGUCUCUUGUUUUCUUGAGACAUCUCUUGGUCACCCUCAAGCAUAUGUACAAGCCAGUUAGGAAGAAGUAAGUACUGAUGACAAGAAGGAGUGUGAGAUGAGAAACAGUAGCCUUUUCUUUGUCUGUAGCAUCUCAAGUUUUAUAGUCUCUGGGAUCUUCUCUCUGAUUAGAAAGUGCUUCUUUUCCACCUGGCAAGGUGGCACACACCUGUAAUCCCAACACUUUGAGAGGCUGUGCUGGGUGGAUUGCUUGGGCCCAGAAGUUUAAGACCAGCCUGGGAAACAUGGCAAAACCCUGUCUCUACAAAAUAAAAUAAAAUAAUGCAAAAAAAGAGAGAGCAACUGCUUCAUUGCUUUUCUAAAACGUUGUUGAGCUAUUUAAAGCCUAUGAUAACGGGGGUUUAUUUGCACUUACUUCCCUUCAUUUUAGUUGAAUUCAAGCUUAUGUCUUCAGAUUUUUAUUGACUUAGUUACCUUAUACUGUUUUUAGUGGAUUGCCGUGAAGUAGGGUUCUGUUGGUUGAGCACAAGGGAAGCAGAGAGCUGGAUGGAGCCAUUAUCUCAGACUUAAGUCAAGCGCUGAUUGAAAUUUCUCUUGUCCCAAACUCCUAGUGGUCCUGCACUCAGGAGAUAGGGAAGGUCGCUGACGAUACUGAGUCUUUUCCACAGUGCUUGCUUCUUUUUAGCAGCCUCAGAUGGAUCCCUGCCCCUAAACUGGGGCUGUUUCUCUCCUUCUCAACCUAAUUGUGUGCCAUGAGGAAAUAAAGAAAGAAAGAGAGAAAGAGAGAAAGAAAGAAAGAAAGAAAGAAAGAAAGAAAGAAAGAAAGAAAGAAAGAAAAGGAAGGAAGGAAGGAAGGAAGGAGAGGAAGGAAGGAAAAGAGAGAAAGAGAGAGAGGAAGGAAGGAAGGAAAGGAAGGGAGGGAGGGAGAGAGAGAGAAAGAAAGAAAAAGAAAGAAGAAAAGAAAGAAGGAAAGAGAGAAGGAGAAAGAAGAAAGAAAAAGAAAGGAAAAGAAGAAAGAAAAGGAAAGAAAAGAAGAAAAGAAAAGAAAAGAAAGAGCUUGUGUUAAAAGCUGCCUAAUUUCCCAUUCCUCCUUGGCUGAUCAUCUAAUUCAUUCAGUGAUGUCAACCCCAGAAGGAGACUCAGUUUUUCUUUGUCUCCAACAUCCUACAGGGGCACUAAGAAGGAGGGCACCAAAAAUGGAAUGCUUCAUAGCACAAGGGAAAAAUUACAAGAAAUCCAAACUCUUUUAAAUAUUUGUUGUUACUUGAACCUUUAAAUUUAAAAAACGAUUUUAUGUCUCUUCUUCCUUAACAGCAUUUCUCUCAUCCAGAGCCAAAUGCCAACGGAGACAUAAAGAGGGGGCACAAGUGGGAUUCAUCCCACCUUACCCUUAGGUAGGAAUUUGCUGCUUUCAGAGUGUAUUCAUCUACAAACUACACUGGAUUCUUGGAAGAAUUUUUUUGUAAAAGUGGCAGGACAAAUGUUAUCCUUUUACAGAUGAGGAAAGAUGGCACAGAGACGUUGUGCACUUGCCUGAGGCCACACAGCCUGACCUUGAACUCCACUUUUCUUUUGAUUCACCAGGCUGAGUGCCUCAUUUUAAGGUACAUUUGACAUUGAGCAUCAUCUGAUGACACCUCCUGGGGGUGGUCUGUACCAAUGCCCUUGGGGUGCGUUUUGUACGUAUUCAAACACCAAAUAUUUAUAGAGGUUCUACUUAAUGUCUGCCAGCUUGUGCCACCCUACUGCUGGCUGUAGGAGGAAGUGGUAUGUGGGGAGGGGUGGGAGAAAGGGUGGUUAUAAUAACUUUAGAGCUGAGGAACACCCUUUUAAACCAAUCCAUUAAUUUUUACACGCGGAGAACUGAGCACAAGCUUUUGAGUGUCUUGUCCAAGUACCUGUUGUCUGUGGCAGGGCAGGAACUGGAACCUAGAGUUUCAUAUGCCCAGUGCCCACUCUGCUUUCAUUCUGAGCAUUGGGCAGCCCCUCCCCUUGUCCUGUUUCUCUCCUGGUUUCCCGGUGUGUGUGUGUGUGUGUGUGUGUGUGUGUGUGUUGCUUGCGGGUGGAGGUUUAGUGAUUUUCAUCAACUCUGUGUUGACUGGUGUUGCAGAGUGUUUUGCAAGCUCUCUGGGUGAAGGCCAGUUUACAAACAUUUACACUGUGCUACCAAGGGUACAAGGGAAGGCUGCUUUUCUUGGGAAUGAAGCUGGGAGCAGGGAGGGGACUACAGAGGCAUGCGAAAAAGAAAAGAGAAUUGCAAGCUGCUUGCUGGAGGAAUGGCCCUUUGUUGCCAGGGAAGUAACCCACAUAGGGCUGGAGCCCCACCGACCCAGAAAAAAGAACGGUGUUAGAGACCGGGAAGCUAGGACUCAUCAGAGACAAAACGUUGGCCCAGCGUGUGCAGAGAAGAAUCUGUCCAAGCAGGAAAGAGCAGAACUACUUCAACUGCAGCUGGAUUUUGGGACCUGAUGCCCAGAACCCUGGACGGGCAGAUCACCAUGGAGAAGACGCCCAGUUACUUCGUCACGCGGGAGGCCCCUGCGCGCAUCUCGGCCAUGUCCAAGGACACCAAGCUCAUCGUGGUGGUGCGGGACCCGGUGACCAGGGCCAUCUCGGACUACACGCAGACGCUGUCCAAGCGGCCCGACAUCCCCACCUUCGAGAGCUUGACGUUCAAAAACAGGACAGCGGGCCUCAUCGACACGUCGUGGAGCGCCAUCCAGAUCGGCAUCUACGCCAAGCACCUGGAGCACUGGCUGCGCCACUUCCCCAUCCGCCAGAUGCUCUUCGUGAGCGGCGAGCGGCUCAUCAGCGACCCGGCCGGGGAGCUGGGCCGCGUGCAAGACUUCCUGGGCCUCAAGAGGAUCAUCACGGACAAGCACUUCUACUUCAACAAGACCAAGGGCUUCCCCUGCCUGAAGAAGGCGGAGGGCAGCAGCCGGCCCCAUUGCCUGGGCAAGACCAAGGGCAGGACCCAUCCUGAGAUCGACCGCGAGGUGGUGCGCAGGCUGCGCGAGUUCUACCGGCCUUUCAACCUCAAGUUCUACCAGAUGACCGGGCACGACUUUGGCUGGGAUUGAGCAGACCCGGGCUAUGUACCUUACCCACGUGGCUUAUCUAUUGACAGAGAUUAUAUGUAUGUAAAAUGUACAGAAAUCUAUUUUAUAAUAAUUUAUUUUUAAUUCAUAAGCAAUUAAUUCACUAAGCUGCCUAGCCACACUCUUUAGAGAGUUAGCUUCAUAAUCUGUUAACAUUCCAAAGUGUUUAACUCUAGUAUUUCGUUCUCUUCUUCACAAUUGAUGGUGCUUCUAUUUUUUCUUCUCCCCUACCUGUUAUAUUUAAAACAAAGAAAAGCACAACUUGAGAUUUUUGUUGUUACGGGUAUUCAGCCUUCAGUCACCGUCUGAGUUCUCCAGUUGCUGCCUCCUUGUCUUGUCUUGGGUCUCCCAUUCCAGCUUCCCUGUCUCUUCCUGCCUGUGUACCUCGUAGGAACGCUGAGCUGCCUCAACAGGGCUGUAUUCUGAAGGGCAGGCCUCAUGCAGCAGCCUCCUUGCAGAUGUGGUGUCCCGUCCAAUGAUGUAGCCUGAAAGCCACAGCCCUAGGGUUCUGUCCCUCCCUCCAUUCAGCACAUGGGGAAAUUUCUCACUCCCUUUACAGGGACAUCCACAUCCUUUUUUUUUCUUUUUUUUUUUUUUUUUUUUUUGAGAUGGAGUCUUGCUCUUGUUGCCCAGGCUGGGGCGUAAUGGUGUGAUAUAUGCUUACCACAACCUCUGGCUCCCGGUUCAAGCGAUUCUCCUGUCUCAGCCUCCCAAGUAUCUGGGAUUACAGGCAUGCACCACCAUGCCUGGCUAAUUUUGUAUUUUUAGUAGAGACGGGGUUUCUUCAUGUUGGUCAGGCUGGUAUCAAACUCCCGACCUCAGGUGAUCCGCCUGCCUUGGCCUCCAAAGUGUUGGGAUUAUAGGCGUGAGCCACUGCGCCCGCUAUCCACAUCCUUCUAGAGUCAGAAUGGUAGGGUCUGUUGACUUCAGCUUUUGAUUUUGCAGGAUGGCCCUGUGUCCUCCUCUGCCCCAUUCCCUGGUUCAUUAACCAGUUUGAAGUGUAUGUAGAUUGUUGCCCCGUCUUUCCCAGGUCACAUGUGUGAGAUGCCUGGGUGCUGCUUCAGAAAUCAAGAUGAUCUCCUUUAAUUUGCAUGAAACUACACCAUGCUGCGUUCCCCAGGCAGACAGUUCUGCUUUGACACACCAAAGAAUCCCGUAGGCUAGCAGAGCCACCAGCACAAACCAAGGGCGCUGGGUGUCGAGACUCAGAGGGGUCAGCUGUGUCCCUCGGCAUCAGCGUCUACCAAGGUGCUGCUAGGUACAGAGCCAGCCAGUGUUGGGCAGCAGGCUCACAGCCUCAAUAGGGAGAAAAGACAAAGGCCUCAAAAUGACAGGCAGCCUGACAGAGGAAGGAGUCUGACACCUCAGCUUGAUGCGUCUUUGGAAUUCCUAGCUCAUCUCAGAAUUAUAUCUUAGAGUGAUAAUAUGGGUGGUAGCCAGUGGCCAAACAGCAAGAACUAAGAGUGGCCCUUGCAAAAAAAGGUUGGGAAAGCUGGGCCCAUAUUGCCUGUAAACCCUUGAGCCUGAUGCUCAUACAGCUGUCCCUUGUUUUAGCCAGGUCUUGACAGAAGGGUUACCAGCACUGUCACUGCUCUACAGAAUGCUCUCCCCGUGCCUCUCUGUUGAUUUAUAACAGUUGGGUAACCAGAUAGCAAUAUAGUGGCAAUUGAGUAGCCAUAUAGUAAUACAGGGGCAGUUGGUUAAACAUAUAGCAAUAUCACAUAAUGAUAUGUUUAAUUUAACCUCAGUUUUUUAAACCAGAAUGCUUCUACCAUAAAAGAAUUGUGAUUUCAGUUAUACUUCCAUCAAGGAAUAUGUGGGAAGAUAUACAUAUUGUCAAAAUGGUUGGGAUGGGAUAGUUACAAAGGACACUUUUGUAUGUUGUAUGGGAUCACUUGCCUGAUAGUAUAAGGAACAUUGUAUGAAAAGAUGAAAAGAUACUUCAUUUUUAGAAACUGAUCAGAGAUGUCACUGGUCUUUAAGUGAUGUCUUGAAAAUCCAGUAUGUAUUUGCCCAAAAGUUUUAGCCUACAUCUAGCUAGCUUACACUUAGCAGCCAAACCAUCAUUGUGUAGGUUCUGUUUUGGAGGAAGCUCAUGGGGGAUCUGUGUAUUUCUUAGGUUUCUCCCUGUUCUCCAAUGUUUUAUCCAUUUCGUAGCUUUUUUACUGUCUCCAGAAAGUAGUGUGGGACCUGCACUUAGGGGAAUACCAGAAUCAUAGCGUGGUUCUGCCUUCUUGAUGAGUGAUUGUGAAAAACACCUGCAUAAGGGUGCUAAUUGGUUGUGUAUUUUUUCAUUUAUUUGAAAUCAAACUGAGAACACCUCUUUUCGGUUUACAGCAUAACAUGGCUUGAAGUAAAAGGCAGUAUCCAAGUCCUUCACCUGGUCUUGCCCUGUCUACUUUCUGAUCAUUCUGAUGGUCUGAUGUGGCUGUUGAUGUGGAACUGCAGAAGAGUUCAGAGAAGAGUAUGCAACAAAGCCAUAGGAAAACACACAGGAGCUUUUCCCUCCCCUUCAGGUCCCCGCCCUCUUUCCAAGCUGGACAAUUUUUUAUUAAGUUGUUUAUUCCCUGCCUUAAAACUGAAACAGGAAAUUUUCUGGUAGAAGGAGGGUCAUUUAGUCACGAACACUGAAGUGGGUCAAAAUUCUAUUCUGGGUCAAAUCCUUGAAUUCAAACAGAUGUCCAUAAUCAGUACUGAUGGAAUAGAGCAAGUUUUUCUAUGUAAGACAAAUAAAUCAAACAUCAUGUGCAUCUCCUCAUAAGGGUCUGCAAGGGUCUGAUGGUUUAAAGUUCCUAACAGAUCUGGUUGCAGCAUCUGCCGGAGCUUGCACCCCAUCAUCGGACGGUCAUCUUCCUGCUGCAGAAGUUAGGUAACAUAAGACUUAGAUUUCUUCCUGUUCUAGCAAUCUGCAAGACCACCAGGCUUAACUUUUUAGCUGCCAGAAGACAAACCCCCUUUUCUGUUUCGGCAAUUUGUCCUGGCACGUGUUUUGGACUUCCUCCGAUUUACACGAAAAGCUCUGAUAUUCAUUGGAGUACUUUAUUUUUUUUCCUCAGUUUUGUUUCUUUUCUCAUGUAAAAACAAACAAAAAGGUCAACAAAAAAAAAUUGAGGUUUUUCUUGUUUCUAUCUAGUUCAUGCUUUCUUUGCGGUGUUUGAACAGUAGUCUGUUAACUUAGUAGGUGGUACCUGGAAAGGUAUUUUAAGUAUAGUGACUGUUUAAUAAAUACUUAAUUGGAUGAUGGAGGAGGAGAAAUUGUUUUCUUCCCAGGAUUCUCUUUGGGGGUCAUUUUGUGUGACAGAUAUAUUUUAGACAUUUGGAGAAACAGUUUCAGAUCCUGCCAGGAUAUUUUUGUAAAAAAGGAAAAUGGAAGAUUCCAAUAAACUAGAAACAGUACGUAUCUAAGAUGCUGACACAGAAGCUAAUGUGACUUUUCAGCUUAUCAAGAGGAUGGCCAAUAAAACUUAAAGGUGUGGUUAGAUGUUUUCUCACUUUUGUGACAUUAAUUUAUCACUGAGUCUCAUUCAACCAAGUAAUCUAAAAUACUGUGCAAAUUCUAGCAGUAUGUCUUCGAUAACUUGGAUGUUAGGAUAGCCAAUAUGUACAAAAAAUUAAAUCAAGUAUUUUGUCCUAUGUAUAACACAAAUUAAUUUUACACAGAGAAAGAUGUUUCUAGGCAAGUGAAAUUCUGGUAAUUCAUACUAUUUCUUUGUAUGAACAAAUAAAAUAUAUUUUGCCAA